CUUGGUGUUGCCCUCCCAUCUCUAUGGCCUGGCUCUGGCCGUGCCUUGCACAGAUCAUGCUCUGCCCUGCGUGUCCCAGCCUGGGCCCAGCCCUCGUCCUACCACAUUCCUGACCCCAGCCAUACCCUUGUUCUGGCCGUGACCCUGCCGUGGCCCUCUCCUGGCCCUUCCUUGGUCCUGCCCUGCCCUUCCAUGCCCUGGCCUUGCCCUCACCCUGCAUUGGCCCUGCACUGGUCCUGCCCUGCCCUGGCACUGCCUUGGCCCCGGCCCUGCCUUCUCCCUGGUCUUGCCUUUGCCCUGCCCUGGCCUGACCCCAGGCCUACUGAGUCCAUGAAAUGGCCCUGGACCUGCCUUGCCAUCGUCUGUCCUGGCCCUGUAUUGUCCCCACCAUGCUCUGGUCCAGCGCUUGCCCUGGCCCUGUUGCUAGUCCUGCCACUGUUAUGGCCCUGCCCUGUUUUUGGCCAUGCCCUGUGCUACCCUAGCCCUGCCCUGCCUUGGCCUUGGCCCUACCAUGGCCUUCUCCUACCCUGGCCUGGCCCUACACUGGCCUUUUCUACUCUGGCCUUGCCCUUCCCUGGUCUUGCCUUGCCCUGGCCUUGCCCUGCCCUGGCCUUGGCUUUGCCUUAUCCUGGUCCUGGUUCUGCCCUGACCCUGGCCUUGCUCUGGAUCCUCUCUGGUUCUGCUUUCUCCCUGGCCCUGCCCUUGCUCUGGCCCUGUCCCUGGCCCAGCCUUGACCCUGACCCUGGCCCUGACAAUCCCCAGGUCUGACACUGGCCAUGCUUGGCCCUGGCCCCUCCUUUUGGCCCUGCCCUGGCCCUGCCUUGGCCCUGUGCUAUCUUAGUCCUGCCCUGGCCCUGAACUCACCCUGGCCCUACCCUCACCCUACACUGGCCCCGCCCUACCCUGACCUUGCCCUGCCCUGGCCCUGCCUUUGGCCUGCUCUGGCUCUGGUUCUGCCCUGGCCUUGCCCUUGCCCUGGACCCUCCCUGGCCAUGUUUUUUCCAUGGUCCUUCUCUGGCCUUGCCCUUGCCCUGUCCCCUUUCUGGUCCUGCCAUAUUUCUGGCCCUGUCCUGUCCAUGUCCUGGACCUGACUCUGGCCCUGGACCUCCCUGUCCCUGCCCUGCCAUACCCUGGCCCGUUCCUUGCUCUACACUGACCCUGCCCUGCCUUGGCCCUGCGCUACCCUAGCCCUGCCCUGGCCUUCUGCUGACCCUGAUCCUGCCAUGGCCCUGGCCCUGCCAUGUCCCUGCCCUGGCCCUGGUUCUGCCCUGCUUCUGGCCCUGGCCUUGGUCCUCUCAUGUCCCUGGCCGUGACCCUGCCCCUGGAUUUUCUCUGGCCAUGACCCUGCCCCUGUUCUGUCCUAUCCCUGGCCCUGUCUCAGUUCUGUCCUAGCCCUGGCCUUUCACAGUACUUUAUGCUUAGUAAGGACUCCAUGGUGUCUGUGAGUUGAAUGUAGUGUUCAUAGUAUCUGCCAAAACAGAAAGAAAAAA